GAAAAGGUGUUGGGUAAAUAUGCAGCUCUAGGGAACAUAUCAAAGGACAGAUAUAGAAGGUACAGCCCAAACUCAGAAACCUCUCUUAACACAGCUCUCAACCCAACUCCUGACACCAUGGCCAGCUGUUCCACCAGUGGGACCUGUGGCUCCAGCUGCUGCCAGCCAAGCUGCUGUGAAACUAGCUGCUGCCAGCCAAGCUGCUGCCAGACCAGCUCCUGCGGAACCGGCUGUGGCAUUGGUGGUGGCAUUGGCUAUGGCCAGGAGGGCAGCGGUGGAUCUGUGAGCACCCGUAUCAGGUGGUGCCACCCAGAUUGCCACGUGGAGGGCACCUGCCUGCCCCCCUGCUACCUGGUAAGCUGCACACCCCCAUCCUGCUGCCAGCUGCACCACGCCGAGGCCUCCUGCUGCCGCCCGUCCUACUGUGGACAGUCCUGCUGCCGCCCAGCCUGCUGCUGCCACUGCUGUGAGCCCACCUGCUAAAAGCCAGGUUGCUGAUCGCUUAAGAAUGAAAGGGGAAGCACAGCAAAAUUGUGCUGAUUUCUGAAGAACUGUUCGAUUUUACUUGGAUGCUAAGUACCAUGAUGUUGUUAAGCUGCUCAGAGAUAAUGAAACUCCUAGUUAGGACACUGUGGAUGUGCCGAAUUCACUUACUGAAAGAUGUAUCAAUCAGUGUUCUGGAUAGCUUGCGUUGCUUGAGCAGAGGACCAGGAUGGAAUAGUUCAUCAUUUCAGUGACAUCUCUGCUCCCCCAACUCUCUCUUGAUGCUCAUGCAUCUUCAGACCUGGUUUUUCCUUGAAUAUCUCUGAUUAAUCCAAAUAAAAUGUUUUAAUGUGCAAAGCAAA